ACUCUUCCCCUCCCACCUUCUCUCCCCUCCUCUCUGCUUUAAUUUUCUCAGAAUUCUCUGGACUGAGGCUCCAGUUCUGGCCUUUGGGGUUCAAGAUCACUGGGACCAGGCCGUGAUCUCUAUGCCCGAGUCUCAACCCUCAACUGUCACCCCAAGGCACUUGGGACGUCCUGGACAGACCGAGUCCCGGGAAGCCCCAGCACUGCCGCUGCCACACUGCCCUGAGCCCAAAUGGGGGAGUGAGAGGCCAUAGCUGUCUGGCAUGGGCCUCUCCACCGUGCCUGACCUGCUGCUGCCACUGGUGCUCCUGGAGCUGUUGGUGGGAAUAUACCCCUCAGGGGUUAUUGGACUGGUCCCUCACCUAGGGGACAGGGAGAAGAGAGAUAGUGUGUGUCCCCAAGGAAAAUAUAUCCACCCUCAAAAUAAUUCGAUUUGCUGUACCAAGUGCCACAAAGGAACCUACUUGUACAAUGACUGUCCAGGCCCGGGGCAGGAUACGGACUGCAGGGAGUGUGAGAGCGGCUCCUUCACCGCUUCAGAAAACCACCUCAGACACUGCCUCAGCUGCUCCAAAUGCCGAAAGGAAAUGGGUCAGGUGGAGAUCUCUUCUUGCACAGUGGACCGGGACACCGUGUGUGGCUGCAGGAAGAACCAGUACCGGCAUUAUUGGAGUGAAAACCUUUUCCAGUGCUUCAAUUGCAGCCUCUGCCUCAAUGGGACCGUGCACCUCUCCUGCCAGGAGAAACAGAACACCGUGUGCACCUGCCAUGCAGGUUUCUUUCUAAGAGAAAACGAGUGUGUCUCCUGUAGUAAAGUCCUGCUCUGUCGCCCAGGCUGGAAUGCAGUGGCGCGAUCUCGGCUCACUGCAACCUCUGCCUCCCAGAUUCAAGCAAUUCUCCUGCUUCAGCCUCCCAAGUAGCUGGGAUUACAGCUGUAAGAAAAGCCUGGAGUGCACGAAGUUGUGCCUACCCCAGAUUGAGAAUGUUAAGGGCACUGAGGACUCAGGCACCACAGUGCUGUUGCCCCUGGUCAUUUUCUUUGGUCUUUGCCUUUUAUCCCUCCUCUUCAUUGGUUUAAUGUAUCGCUACCAACGGUGGAAGUCCAAGCUCUACUCCAUUGUUUGUGGGAAAUCGACACCUGAAAAAGAGGGGGAGCUUGAAGGAACUACUACUAAGCCCCUGGCCCCAAACCCAAGCUUCAGUCCCACUCCAGGCUUCACCCCCACCCUGGGCUUCAGUCCCGUGCCCAGUUCCACCUUCACCUCCAGCUCCACCUAUACCCCCGGUGACUGUCCCAACUUUGCGGCUCCCCGCAGAGAGGUGGCACCACCCUAUCAGGGGGCUGACCCCAUCCUUGCGACAGCCCUCGCCUCCGACCCCAUCCCCAACCCCCUUCAGAAGUGGGAGGACAGCGCCCACAAGCCACAGAGCCUAGACACUGAUGACCCCGCGACGCUGUACGCCGUGGUGGAGAACGUGCCCCCGUUGCGCUGGAAGGAAUUCGUGCGGCGCCUAGGGCUGAGCGACCACGAGAUCGAUCGGCUGGAGCUGCAGAACGGGCGCUGCCUGCGCGAGGCGCAAUACAGCAUGCUGGCGACCUGGAGGCGGCGCACGCCGCGGCGCGAGGCCACGCUGGAGCUGCUGGGACGCGUGCUCCGCGACAUGGACCUGCUGGGCUGCCUGGAGGACAUCGAGGAGGCGCUUUGCGGCCCCGCCGCCCUCCCGCCCGCGCCCAGUCUUCUCAGAUGAGGCUGCGCCCCUGCGGGCAGCUCUAAGGACCGUCCUGCGAGAUCGCCUUCCAACCCCACUUUUUUCUGGAAAGGAGGGGUCCUGCAGGGGCAAGCAGGAGCUAGCAGCCGCCUACUUGGUGCUAACCCCUCGAUGUACAUAGCUUUUCUCAGCUGCCUGCGCGCCGCCGACAGUCAGCGCUGUGCGCGCGGAGAGAGGUGCGCCGUGGGCUCAAGAGCCUGAGUGGGUGGUUUGCGAGGAUGAGGGACGCUAUGCCUCAUGCCCGUUUUGGGUGUCCUCACCAGCAAGGCUGCUCGGGGGCCCCUGGUUCGUCCCUGAGCCUUUUUCACAGUGCAUAAGCAGUUUUUUUUGUUUUUGUUUUGUUUUGUUUUGUUUUUAAAUCAAUCAUGUUACACUAAUAGAAACUUGGCACUCCUGUGCCCUCUGCCUGGACAAGCACAUAGCAAGCUGAACUGUCCUAAGGCAGGGGCGAGCACGGAACAAUGGGGCCUUCAGCUGGAGCUGUGGACUUUUGUACAUACACUAAAAUUCUGAAGUUAAA